ACCAGUCGCCUGUGUACCUUUGUACUUUCUACAGUGAAAGUUGCUACAGGAUCUCCCUUUCUCAAUAAAUUCAUCUGCGGUGGAGAAAAUCAGCAUGAGUACUACAGGCCAAGUCAUCAGAUGCAAAGCAGCCAUACUCUGGAAGCCUGGUGCACCAUUUUCUAUUGAAGAGGUAGAAGUGGCCCCACCAAAGGCAAAGGAAGUUCGCAUAAAGGUUGUGGCCACCGGACUGUGUGGUACAGAGAUGAAAGUGUUGGGGAGUAAACACUUGGACCUCUUGUAUCCCACCAUCUUGGGCCAUGAAGGGGCUGGAAUCGUUGAGAGUAUUGGAGAAGGAGUAAGCACAGUGAAACCAGGUGACAAAGUUAUCACACUCUUUCUGCCACAGUGUGGAGAAUGUACCUCUUGCCUGAAUUCUGAGGGCAAUUUUUGUAUACAAUUCAAACAGUCAAAAACCCAACUGAUGUCUGAUGGUACCAGCAGGUUUACCUGCAAGGGAAAAUCAAUAUAUCACUUUGGUAAUACCAGCACCUUCUGUGAAUACACAGUGAUAAAGGAAAUCUCAGUUGCCAAGAUUGAUGCAGUCGCUCCUCUAGAGAAAGUAUGCCUAAUUAGCUGUGGCUUUUCCACUGGGUUUGGUGCUGCAAUCAAUACUGCCAAGGUGACUCCAGGUUCUACCUGUGCUGUGUUUGGCCUGGGAGGAGUCGGCUUGUCUGUUGUCAUGGGUUGUAAAGCAGCAGGAGCAGCCAGGAUCAUUGGAGUGGAUGUCAACAAGGAGAAAUUUAAGAAGGCACAGGAAUUGGGUGCUACUGAGUGCCUCAACCCUCAGGACUUAAAGAAACCCAUUCAAGAAGUUUUAUUUGAUAUGACAGAUGCUGGUAUAGACUUCUGCUUUGAGGCCAUUGGAAAUCUGGACGUUCUGGCAGCUGCCCUCGCCUCCUGCAAUGAGAGCUAUGGGGUCUGUGUGGUUGUUGGGGUGUUGCCUGCCAGUGUUCAACUCAAAAUCAGUGGCCAGUUGUUCUUCUCAGGACGUUCUUUGAAGGGUUCUGUUUUUGGAGGCUGGAAGAGCAGACAGCACAUCCCUAAACUGGUUGCUGAUUAUAUGGCAGAGAAGUUGAAUCUAGAUCCACUAAUUACUCAUACUCUGAAUCUUGAUAAAAUCAAUGAAGCAGUUGAAUUAAUGAAAACUGGAAAAUGGUAAACUGCCCACAUAAAUUUUAUGUCUGUGUGUUUGAGACCAAGAGAAAGGGUGUAUUGGCUUGGGAGUAGAAGAAGGGUCGUCCCUGCUGCAGAAGCUGUAUACUGAUAAUUGAAGAGGCUUUCAGGAAUUUGUAAAGCAUCUCCUUCCCCUCUGCAUUUUGUUUUAUUUCUAGCUAAUAAAAUACAUAAUCCUGAAAGUAUUUAAGUGUUCACCUACCGUUACUUUUGCCAUUAGCAUUGUAUUUCCAAUAUGGAUUUUUUUUUUACAUGACAUAUUAAUGGAAGUCAGCUUAUAAAAUUGUAGCUCAAGUUUAAAAACAUAAGAAGGUAGUUCACAAAUAGGCCAUUGUUGUAUUUGUUGUUCUACUUUGGGGGAGAAGAGGAAUUAUUCAUAGGAUUCCUAAUUCUGAAUCCUAUCUUUGACCCAAAAAACAGAAACCAGCCAUAACCCAGAAACUGGCAUUCCCCACACGAGUAUAAGCUUGCUUACCUACUUUUUACCCUUGGAGUUUCAUGUCAUUUUAAAAAAUCUUCCCAUGGCUUAUUUAAUCUUCUCAUUUUUCACCUAAAGAGAAAAAAAAUCUAGUUUACUGCUCUACAAAGUGAGAAUUUGAAAUCCAAAACACAAAUGUUGCUCUAAAAAUGUUCCAACCUUUUUUCUCUUCUUCUUUUUUUCAGUAUCCGCUGUAUCCUGUUACUUUAAGUACAAUGUAAUACAUGCAAGACCCAAAGGAUAUUUCACCAACUCAAUGGCAUUUGAUGUAAUUUUCAUGAUUUAGAAGAAUUAUUCACCCAAUCCCAUUUCUAUAUUCUGACUUCUGAUUCACUCCGCAGUGGACCUAUAUCUGGCUUCUGACCUAACCAUUUCAUCAAAAUUGUUCUUACGUAACCCAGUGUCACCAAGGAUCAGCCUCCUUUUCAGAGCUAGAUUAAGGUUGGCUUGAAUCACUCAACUCCACAUCCUUCAGACAUAAAAGGUCAAUGCAAGAUGCUCCCAUUUUCAUAGUUCCUCUACCUGUGGACCUUUAUAUUCUUGUACACUAUAUGUCUCUCUCACAGGCCUAGACAUGAAACUCUGCCAUUUUACUCUAAAGAAACAAAACUCCGCAUUAAUGAGUUUAUUGAAGAUUCAGGUUAACCUGAAUCAAGUUAACCCAGUCUCAAAUGCUCACUUAUCCUAUCUCCUUGGCACAAAUCUCUCCUCUCCUGGAUUGCCAAAGAAAAUUCAAAUUAUUCUUCAAUUAGUCAGGAUGAUUUGACUAUCAGCAGUUCAUAGUACCCAUCUUCAUAACUAAGCCACCUAGGGAUCCAGCAGAAAAAAAAGGGAUGAGGGGAGUCAUCAUACAGGAGGUGGAUCAUUUAGCAGGAUCCACACUUCCUACAAAGCGGUUGUAAUAUUAAAUAACAAAACUGUUUUUUAUUCCAAUCUUCACAUAAAACAGGAAUAAUUGUAUACUUUCUUACUAAUGUGUUCCAUGGAGUUUUUCCUCCAAGAAGUGGCUUAGGGGAAAAUGAGCCCCAGUAAUGCUUUGUGGCAUCCAAUCCUUCUACCCCGACCCUUUGACUUUCUGCCCCAGCCCCUCUUAGUUCUCCUAGAAUUAGGACUAAGGUUAAGUGCCCUCUUGGGAUAUGACUUCCUUCCCUUCCUCUUGAUACAAAAAGAGCCUAUUACCAACCCUCAUACACACAAGAGUUCCCUUCCUAGUUGCAGACUCUUCUGCUCCAGCUGGACUCCCCUAGCUCUGGACUCCCACUAGAUCACACAGGGGUCCCUGCAUGUCAGUAAACUUUGGAUGACCUUGGGAGACCAAAAAAUGGAAUAUCAUUUUUUGAUCUAAACAAAAUAGUUUCCUGAUUUAACACUGGCCAGGAAGGUGGGCUGCACCCUCAGUCUCUCUCUCCCAUCAUGGUUUUCACAUGAUAUCAAAGGACUCUCAUAACAGUCUGAUUCUUAUGAGUUGGGCAUCCUGUGUUUCCCUUUAGGGGCCUGCUUCCUUCAAAUAGAGGAGAUGGGUGCUAUGAAACCUAUUCACUCUGGACUUGGGAUGGCUCUUCUCCAUCUUCCCAAGUCUGAGCUGGAGCCUCCAUGCCCAACUCUGCUCUGCUCUUCUAUUUCCUGACAGCAGCUAAGGCAUGUUCCUGUUCUGCCCCCAAAUUGACCUUACUAACAGUGAGAACUUGGAGGAGUCUUCGGGUCUUGGGAAAUCCAAGUUUUCCCGGAAACGUUUUGUUGUAAACAGUGUCCACACUCUUUGCUCCAAUAAAGCUCGGUUCCUUAAGCCA